GAGACCAGAGAUCUAGCGACUGAAGCAGCAUGGCCAAGCCGUGUGGGGUGCGCCUGAGCGGGGAAGCCCGCAAACAGGUGGAGGUCUUCAGACAGAAUCUUUUCCAGGAGGUCUUCAGUUUCCUCAUUUGCAAGUCUUGGACCCAGUGAUUUCCAAAGGCCCUUCCAGUUCCAUUUGUCAGACAUCUCAUUGAGCAUAUUCUGUGAUUCCCCUCCCUUGCAAUGUAACCCACAGGCUGAGGAAUUCCUCUACAGAUUCUUGCCACAGAAAAUCAUAUACCUGAAUCAGCUCUUGCAAGAGGACUCCCUCAAUGUGGCUGACUUGACUUCCCUCCGGGCCCCACUGGACAUCCCCAUCCCAGACCCUCCACCCAAGGAUGAUGAGAUGGAAACAGAUAAGCAGGAGAAGAAAGAAGUCCAUAAGUGUGGAUUUCUCCCUGGGAAUGAGAAAGUCCUGUCCCUGCUUGCCCUGGUUAAGCCAGAAGUCUGGACUCUCAAAGAGAAAUGCAUUCUGGUGAUUACAUGGAUCCAACACCUGAUCCCCAAGAUUGAAGAUGGAAAUGAUUUUGGGGUAGCAAUCCAGGAGAAGGUGCUGGAGAGGGUGAAUGCCGUCAAGACCAAAGUGGAAGCUUUCCAGACAACCAUUUCCAAGUACUUCUCAGAACGUGGGGAUGCUGUGGCCAAGGCCUCCAAGGAGACUCAUGUAAUGGAUUACCGGGCCUUGGUGCAUGAGCGAGAUGAGGCAGCCUAUGGGGAGCUCAGGGCCAUGGUGCUGGACCUGAGGGCCUUCUAUGCUGAGCUUUAUCAUAUCAUCAGCAGCAACCUGGAGAAAAUUGUCAACCCAAAGGGUGAAGAAAAGCCAUCUAUGUACUGAACCCGGGACUAGAAGGAAAAUAAAUGAUCUAUAUGUUGUGUGGA